GGGUCCUCGCCACGUCCCCUUCCCGGAGCUACGCGCCCGGCUGGGUUCCGAUCCGCCGUGUCUCUCGGGGGCGGCUCGCGGGGCAGGGGCGCUCCCGGCUCGGCCGCACGCCCAAGUGUCAUGCGGGAGGUACGCGGGCACGGGACCUCACCGGAGAGAAUGAUGGCUCUGGGAUCUGAAAUCUUUCCUUCCGCAGGAACUGGACACGGCAGUGAGGACCAGCGUAUCCAAGAGGAUGGACUUAGUGAUGGGGAACACCCAGGGACAUGCCCGAGAGCCUCAAGAAACACCUUCAGAUGACAUUGCCCAGCGUCUUACAUUAGAGAACUCUCCAGACAGCCCCCGAGGCCUGGGGCCGGGUGCUGCUCCCAGACUGUGAGCUCGUGGCCACGGGAAGCCUGAGUGCGGCAGAGGCCCCACAGCUGCGCCAAGUGCGGCAAAGCCUCCCGUACAGUUACUCCCUGAGCGGUCAUCUCCGAAGCCCUGCUCAUGAGAAGCCUCCCCUUUGCCCUGACUGUGGAAAGCGUUUCAGCCAGAGCUCCUACCUGCUGCAGCACCGGCAGAUUCACCCAGGGCCGUCAGCCCUGCAAGUGCAAGGCCUGCGGGAGGGGUUUUACUCAGAGCGCAUCCCUCCUCCAGCACUGGCGGGUCCACAGCGACUGGCGAGAGACCUUGUCGCUGUCCCCAGUGCGGCAAGACCUGCUGUGGCCGCUCCAACCUCAUCAAGCACCAGCGAGUCCACUCGGGAGAAGCCAUUCGUCUGCGGGAGUGCGGCAAGGGUUUAGCGGCCAGCUCUGCUGCUGGCUCACCAAGGAGCACACACUGGCCGAAGCCCUGCGUCUGUCCCCAGUACCAGCAGGUUUUUGGGGACCGGUGGAAGCUGAUCGGCCACCAGCGAAUUCACACAGGAGAGUGUGUCCCUUCUGCUGCUGCAGCUGCGGUGACAGUGUCAAUGAGAAGACCUCCCUCUCCCAGCGCGUCCUUCCGCACCCAGGGGAGAAGACCUGCAGGGGUGGGAGCGUGGAGAGCGUCAGCCUCGCACCCAGCUCAGUCGCCCCGGACAGCACCUCUGGGCUCCGGCCCUGUGGGAGCCCCGGGUCCUUCCUUCAACAUCUGCCCCCAUCCACACUCCUGCCCCGACCUCCCUUCCUUUAUCCUGGCCCCCCACUCAGUCUCCAGCCUCUGGUUCCAUCCGGCCUUCCCGCAGUGCCUGCAGUGCCUCUGGGAGGCCUGGAAGUUGCCCAGGUUCCGCCAGCCACCCAGCCGGCAGCUCAGCAGGAGGGGGCGAUGGGGCCCAGAAGCUGUGCGAGCGCGGGACGGGACUCGCGGGAGGCGGUUCAGGCCCCAGGCUACCCUGAGCCAGCCCGGAAGGCCUCGCAGCACAGAGCGGCCGGACCGCUCGGCGAGGCCAGGGCCAGGCUUCAGCGACAGUGCCGAGCUCCUCCACCGCCCUCGAACCCACACUGGAGAGGAGCCCUACCAGUGUUUCCGGUGUGGAAGGCCUCCAGCCGGAGGUCCAACCUGGCCCGACACUGAAGAACCAGCGUGCUGCAGCCCUGGGUGGAAUUGUUGCAGCCGCCGGUGGACUGUGGAUCUGAGAUGCAGUCCCCUCCCUCCACACAGACCCGCUCAGGACGGCUUUUCUGUAUGGCAGAUCUUUCUCAGAAGUGCUGGGGGCUAUUUUGUUUGUUUUUUUUCCCCUGAAUUCUCGCUCCUUUCCCUUAUACAUUAAGGGAUUUAGGCAGGUGCGGCUGCGGGCGGUGACUCACACCUGUAAUCCCAGCGCUUUAAGAGACCGAGGUGGGAGGAUCGCGUGAGCCCGAAGAAUUUGAGACUAGCCUGGGCAGCCUAGCGAGACCGCAUCUCUGUGAAAUAAAAAUAAAACGAGCUGGUGUGGUGGCGCUG